AAUCCACUGCCUAGCAGGUGGCCCAUUCCAGUUGGAGAACGUAGUGAGUCUUUCAGUGGAGCCAGGGUCUGGCCAGGCUGACUUGUACACUAAGCCGAAUCUCAAAAGCCCAGACAGAGUUCCAUUGGUGGAAAGAAAAAGCCGGCUCGCCUUUGAAAGGCUGCCUUUCUUCCAGGUUUGUCGUGAGGAGCUCCGCGAUGUCCUCUCAACAGAGCGCCGUUUCCGCCAAAGGCUUUUCCAAGGGGUCGUCCCAGGGCCCCGCUCCGUGUCCCGCCCCGGCGCCCACCCCGGCGCCCGCCUCCUCCUCCUCCUGCUGCGGCUCCGGCAGGGGCUGCUGCGGCGACUCAGGCUGCUGCGGCUCCAGCUCCACCAGUUGCUGCUGCUUCCCAAGGAGACGCCGCCGACAGCGGAGUAGUGGUUGCUGCUGCUGCGGGGGCGGCAGCCAGAGGUCCCAGCGCUCCAACAACCGGAGCUCAGGAUGCUGCUCCGGCUGCUGAGAGGCCCGCAACCCCCAGCGCUGCGCUAGAGAAACCCGCCCAGCCCAGAGCGGGCCCGCCCCGCUGCGGCUCCCACGCGGGGCUGGGCCUCGGAGUUUGCCCCGUAAAGCGAAUUGCACUUUGAUGUUCAGAAACCCACUUUGUUCUCAGCCACGCAAAACUCCCUGACCCCGAUGUGAUUUUUCUCCCCGGGGAUUCGAGAGCCAUGCGUGGGACACUGGACCCUACUGUCUACACGGGCUUGCACACAGCAGGUGCUCAGCAAAUGUCUAUUGAUUUGAUUGUCUUUUGAAGAUGUCAUAAUAAAGCUUCUACCUCCUGAGAA